ACAUCCAGGGGGGACGCCAAGGGAGCAGGACGGAGCCAUGGACCCCGCCAGGAAAGCAGGUGCCCAGGCCAUGAUCUGGACUGCAGGCUGGCUGCUGCUGCUGCUGCUUCGCGGAGGAGCGCAGGCCCUGGAGUGCUACAGCUGCGUGCAGAAAGCAGAUGACGGAUGCUCCCCGAACAAGAUGAAGACAGUGAAGUGCGCGCCGGGCGUGGACGUCUGCACCGAGGCCGUGGGGGCGGUGGAGACCAUCCACGGACAAUUCUCGCUGGCAGUGCGGGGUUGCGGUUCGGGACUCCCCGGCAAGAAUGACCGCGGCCUGGAUCUUCACGGGCUUCUGGCGUUCAUCCAGCUGCAGCAAUGCGCUCAGGAUCGCUGCAACGCCAAGCUCAACCUCACCUCGCGGGCGCUCGACCCGGCAGGUAAUGAGAGUGCAUACCCGCCCAACGGCGUGGAGUGCUACAGCUGUGUGGGCCUGAGCCGGGAGGCGUGCCAGGGUACAUCGCCGCCGGUCGUGAGCUGCUACAACGCCAGCGAUCAUGUCUACAAGGGCUGCUUCGACGGCAACGUCACCUUGACGGCAGCUAAUGUGACUGUGUCCUUGCCUGUCCGGGGCUGUGUCCAGGAUGAAUUCUGCACUCGGGAUGGAGUAACAGGCCCAGGGUUCACGCUCAGUGGCUCCUGUUGCCAGGGGUCCCGCUGUAACUCUGACCUCCGCAACAAGACCUACUUCUCCCCUCGAAUCCCACCCCUUGUCCGGCUGCCCCCUCCAGAGCCCACGACUGUGGCCUCAACCACAUCUGUCACCACUUCUACCUCGGCCCCAGUGAGACCCACAUCCACCACCAAACCCAUGCCAGCGCCAACCAGUCAGACUCCGAGACAGGGAGUAGAACACGAGGCCUCCCGGGAUGAGGAGCCCAGGUUGACUGGAGGCGCCGCUGGCCACCAGGACCGCAGCAAUUCAGGGCAGUAUCCUGCAAAAGGGGGGCCCCAGCAGCCCCAUAAUAAAGGCUGUGUGGCUCCCACAGCUGGAUUGGCAGCCCUUCUGUUGGCCGUGGCUGCUGGUGUCCUACUGUGAGCUUCUCCACCUGGAAAUUUCCCUCUCACCUACUUCUCUGGCCCUGGGUACCCCUCUUCUCAUCACUUCCUGUUCCCACCACUGGACUGGGCUGGCCCAGCCCCUGUUUUUCCAACAUUCCCCAGUAUCCCCAGCUUCUGCUGCGCUGGUUUGCGGCUUUGGGAAAUAAAAUACCGUUGUAUAUAUUCUGCCAGGGGUGUUCUAGCUUUUUGAGGACAGCUCCUGUAUCCUUCUCAUCCUUGUCUCUCCGCUUGUCCUCUUGUGAUGUUAGGACAGAGUGAGAGAAGUCAGCUGUCACGGGGAAGGUGAGAGAGAGGAUGCUAAGCUUCCUACUCACUUUCUCCUAGCCAGCCUGGACUUUGGAGCGUGGGGUGGGUGGGACAAUGGCUCCCCACUCUAAGCACUGCCUCCCCUACUCCCCGCAUCUUUGGGGAAUCGGUUCCCCAUAUGUCUUCCUUACUAGACUGUGAGCUCCUCGAGGGCAGGGACCGUGCCUUAUGUCUGUGUGUGAUCAGUUUCUGGCACAUAAAUGCCUCAAUAAAGAUUUAAUUACUUUGUAUAGUG